AGAGCGCGGGCUGUACUGAGAGCGCGGCGGGAAGGUAGCGCAGUCGGGCGGCCCGCGGCCCCGGCGCGGCCUCCGCUAGGGCCAAGACCCGCACACCUGCCGGGCCGGGGAGAAGCCGGGGGCCGCGCGCAGGCGAGGACCCGCCGCCCGGCCCGGGGAAGAUCUCAGGACGCGGACCGGGCAGCUCGGGUCCGAGGUGAGCCCGGGCGGAGGACGCGCCCACCGGAGGUGCGGCCUCGGAGCUCCAGACCCAGCCCACUCGGGGCUGGGGUCCCCAGAGGAGGCCGACGGCCGAGGCGGCGUGCGCCGGGAGCCAGCGCGAUCCCUGCGGGAGCGGAGGAGCCGAGCCGGAGGGAGCCGCGGCGCCCGGCCAUGCACCGGGCGCAGUAGCGGGAGGCGCGGGCCCGAUGGCGCGGGCCGGGGCGCGGGGACUGCUCGGCGGCCGCCGUCCUCCCGGCCUCCGGCUCGCGCUCGCGCUUCGGCUCGCGUUGCUGCUGGCGCGGCCGCCGUCGGGCCGCGCGGGAGCCCCCGAGGCGCAGGGUCCCGCGGCGCCCGGCACGACAGCCCCGGAGGGGGGCGACCGCUGCCGCGGCUACUACGACGUGAUGGGCCAGUGGGACCCGCCCUUCAACUGCAGCUCCGGAGCCUACAGCUUCUGCUGCGGCACGUGCGGCUACCGCUUCUGCUGCCACGACGGGCCGCGGCGCCUCGACCAGAGCCGCUGUUCCAACUACGACACGCCGGCCUGGGUCCAGACAGGCCGGCCGCCCGCCCGCGCCCGCGACACCGCAGCGCCCCGGGACCCCGGCCGCGAGCGCAGCCAUACGGCCGUCUACGCUGUGUGCGGCGUCGCAGCGCUGCUGGUGCUGGCCGGCAUCGGGGCGCGCCUGGGACUGGAGAGGGCGCACAGCCCGCGCGCGCGGCGCACAGUGACCAGGGCGCUGACAGAGCUUCUGAAGCAGCCGGGCCCCCAGGAGCCACUGCCUCCCACCCUGGGCCCACCCCUGGGUGGCUGUGUCCAGGUGCAGAUGGGGGACGGCCUCCCCCGGGGCUCCCCCCACAACAGCGCAGGUCCCAGGACUCCGCGCCUGGCUCGAGCGUCGCCUCCGGGCGAGCCGUUCAUGAGGGUGGCACCCCCCGGGCUGGCUGCCGCCGCCGCUGCGCGUGACUCGGAGCCAGGCCCUGUUCCAGGCGCUGGAGGCUGCGGCGAAGACAGGCUUGGCUCGCAGCCUCGCCCGGAGAACGGUCCCCCAGGUUCUCACCGAACGGCCUCGGGGAGAGGACUACGGAGAGGUGACAGCGAGGGCGGAGUGAACCGGGGCAUCGGACCGAGCCGCGUCUCACUCCUCGCUCCAGACAAGAAGCGCCUCAACAACGCGCCCCGGGGGUCGGCCGCCCCGGGGCCCCCGCGCGGCCCGCGGCUGCAGGGCGGCGGCAGCCUGACGCUGCAGCCAGACUACGCCAAGUACGCCACGUUCAAGGCCGCCGCGCUCAAGGCCGCAGAGGCCGCCCCGCGGGACUUCUGUCAGCGUUUCCCCGCCCUCGAGCCGUCCCCGCGGCAACCCCCGGCGCGGGCUCCGCGACCAUCCCCGGACUUGCCUGCGCCGCUGGACGCCUGCCCCUGGGCCCCGCCGGUCUACGCGCCCCCUGCCGCGCCGGGCCCCUAUGCCGCCUGGACCUCCAGUCGCCCGGCCCGGCCCGCCCCGCUCAGCCACCCGACGGCUCGGGCCUUCCAGGUACCCCGGCGACCCGGGCACGCGGCCCGGCGCCAGUUCAGUGUGAAGAUGCCUGAGACCUUCAACCCGCAGCUCCCCGGCCUUUACGGCAGCGCGGGCCGCGGGUCCCGGUACCUAAGGACCAAUAGCAAGACCGAGGUCACCGUGUGAAGCGGGGCCGCGGUGCCCUCGAGGCAUGGGCUGGGGUCCUGUCUGCCCGUCGGAGCCUCAGGCCACAGGGAGAGGAGCGCCUGCCGUAAGGCCAGCUCUUCUGUCUGCCUCAACGGCAGUGGUGUCUUGGAGCCUGCAGGCCGCGGGUUCGUCUUGUAAAUAAGCCCUUUUAUGUGGUUCCUGCCCCUGAGAAUAAAGAAGCCCCAGCGUGGCUGCGAGGCA